GGCGGCGCUUGUUGUUCGGCGGCGGCGGUCGCAGCUCGGGUCCCCCUCGGGCGCCCCCGCCGCCGUCCGCGCGCGGCCAUGGAGCUGGAGGUACCGGACGAGGCGGAGAGCGCUGAGGCGGGGGCCGUGCCCUCGGAGGCGGCGUGGGCGGCAGAGAGCGGGGCGGCGGCAGGUUUGGCUCAGAAGAAGGCGGCCCCAACAGAGGUUCUGUCCAUGACGGCACAGCCGGGCCCUGGCCAUGGGAAGAAGUUGGGCCAUCGAGGUGUGGACGCAUCCGGCGAAACCACCUACAAGAAGACCACCUCCUCCACCCUGAAGGGUGCCAUCCAGCUGGGCAUCGGCUACACCGUGGGCCACCUGAGCUCCAAGCCCGAACGCGACGUGCUCAUGCAGGACUUCUACGUGGUGGAGAGCAUCUUCUUCCCCAGCGAAGGCAGCAACCUCACCCCCGCCCACCACUUCCAGGACUUCCGCUUCAAGACCUAUGCACCUGUCGCCUUCCGCUACUUCCGGGAGCUCUUUGGGAUCCGGCCAGAUGAUUACUUGUACUCCCUGUGCAAUGAGCCGCUGAUCGAGCUGUCCAACCCGGGCGCCAGUGGCUCCCUCUUCUACGUCACCAGCGACGACGAGUUCAUCAUCAAGACCGUCAUGCACAAGGAGGCCGAGUUCCUGCAGAAGCUGCUCCCUGGCUACUACAUGAACCUCAACCAGAACCCGCGGACGCUGCUGCCCAAGUUCUAUGGGCUGUACUGCGUGCAGUCGGGGGGCAAGAACAUCCGCGUCGUGGUCAUGAACAACAUCCUGCCCCGCGUGGUCAAGAUGCACCUCAAGUUCGACCUCAAGGGCUCCACCUACAAGCGGCGCGCCAGCAAGAAGGAGAAGGAGAAGAGCUUCCCCACCUACAAGGACCUGGACUUCAUGCAGGACAUGCCCGAGGGGCUCCUGCUGGACGCCGACACCUUCAGCGCCCUGGUCAAGACGCUGCAGCGGGACUGCCUGGUCCUGGAAAGUUUCAAGAUCAUGGACUACAGCCUGCUGCUGGGCGUGCACAACAUCGACCAGCACGAGCGCGAGCGGCAGGCGCAGGGCGCCCAGAGCACCUCAGAUGAGAAGCGGCCUGUGGGCCAGAAGGCGCUCUACUCCACGGCCAUGGAGUCCAUCCAGGGUGGCGCCGCGCGCGGGGAGGCCAUCGAAUCGGAUGACACGAUGGGCGGGAUCCCCGCUGUGAACGGCCGCGGGGAGCGGCUGCUGCUGCACAUUGGCAUCAUCGACAUCCUGCAGUCCUACAGGUUCAUCAAGAAACUGGAGCACACCUGGAAGGCCCUCGUCCACGAUGGGGACACGGUGUCCGUCCACCGCCCCAGCUUCUAUGCCGAGCGCUUUUUCAAGUUCAUGAGCAACACGGUCUUUCGGAAGAACUCCUCCCUGAAGUCCUCGCCCUCCAAGAAGGGGCGCGGCGGAGCCUUGCUAGCUGUGAAACCGCUGGGGCCCACCGCUGCCUUCUCGGCCAGCCAGAUCCCUAGCGAGCGGGAGGAGGCCCAGUACGACCUGCGGGGGGCCCGCAGCUACCCCACGCUGGAGGACGAAGGCCGGCCCGACCUCCUGCCCUGCACGCCACCUUCUUUCGAAGAAGCCACUACAGCCUCCAUUGCCACGACUCUGUCAUCCACAUCCCUCUCCAUUCCUGAGCGGUCCCCCUCGGAGACGUCGGAGCAGCCGCGGUACAGGCGGCGCACACAGUCGUCUGGACAGGAUGGCAGGCCGCAGGAGGAGCCACCCGCGGAAGAGGAUCUGCAGCAGAUUACAGUGCAGGUGGAGCCUGCGUGCAGCGUGGAGAUUGUGGUCCCCAAAGAGGAGGACGCAGGGGUGGAGGCUUCCCCGGCCGGUGCCUCUGCUGCUGUUGAAGUAGAAACUGCCAGCCAGGCCUCAGACGAGGAGGGCGCACCUGCCAGCCAGGCCUCGGACGAGGAGGACGCGCCCGCCACCGACAUCUACUUUCCCACCGAUGAGAGGAGCUGGGUGUACUCCCCGCUCCACUAUAGCGCCCAGGCCCCCCCGGCCUCCGACGGCGAGAGCGACACAUAAUUUCUAUGCAGCCCCCGACCCAGAGCCGAGCUCCACUUCUGCUCCGGCUGCCCCCGAAGGCGCUGCCCACCCCGCUGAGGCCCAGAGCUCGGGAGAUGCCCGCCUCGCCGCCCCACCGGACCUCGUCCUCCCCCUGCACGGAUGCCGACGGCCGGGCCCCUCCCCGACAAGCCUCCCAGGGCCCCGGCACCCCGGUCGGCAGCCUGCCCCUGUGAGACCCACCCUCCCGAGCGGCCAAUCGCAUUUGAGUCCUUAUUUGGCACAGAGACGGAAGCACGUGUGUGCCGUUUUAGGAAAAGAACAAAAAAGACACAAACAAACCAACCAGAGGGAGAAGAGCCCCUGCCCACUGCACUCUUUGGUUCUCUGCUGUGCCUGCCUGUGUCCUGAGGAAGAAGCCAGGCUGUUCGCGGUGGCCUCUGGGGACCUGAGCCCCGGGGGCCCCAUCGGCCUGCAGAGGGGACGGCUGGGGUCCCGAGCAACUCUGCCUCCAUCCACGUGGGAAGCGGACCCUCCUGCCCUCAGCUUGGGUUUGGGGGCCUCAGUGCAGGACAUCUGGCCUGAACAUCGACUGUGGGGACAGCCCUCGCCCUGCCAAGCACUGCGGCCACUCAGCAGCUAUGUUCCCGCCGCAGUGGGGCCCUGACGCCCACCUCCCAGGUGCCCCUCGAGCAAAAACCUCUGGCGCCUCCAAUCCAGACCCACCACAGCUGGAGGGCCAGGCCUCCUCUUCCCCAGGCUGCCACCCACGCUGGCGGAGCUCAGGGCUGGGGACUUGUCCUUCUCUUCCAACGUAGGCCACUCAGCAACUGGCAUGGAGGGCCCAGGCAACGGAGACGUUUUCUCCAUGGCAGGACAGAGCGGGAGGCCGGGCCUUGGGCCACAGGAGACCAGCUCAGGGCGGAAGGUCAGGCUCCCCGCCCCCUCCACGUGGAGACAUGGCCUAGGGGGCCAGGCCCGGCUCCACAGGAGUCUCCUUCAGGACUGGUGUGGAUGUCCGCCGCCUCUUUCUUGUUUAAGUGAUGUGAUGUCUCCGAGGAGGGGAGAGAAGACUUUGUUUCCGACUCAUCACCCUCCAAGAGGGCAGCGCUCCCAGUGGUGGGACUCAGCCCAGACUGCCCUGGGGCAGCUUCCUGGGCCCGCUGCGCUCAGAGGGUGCUGGUUGGAGGCCAGAGCUCGGCAGAGUCACCCACCCUGCCCUUCCCCAGGACCCCUGAGAGGGGCUUAUUGGUGAUGGCUGUGGGAAUCCCCCACUUCCAAGAUGUGCCCAGGAUGUGAGGAGCUGGAGUGGAAGCUGCACCUUUGGGAAGAAUUCCUCUCCAGACCUGGCAGAGCCUGGUGUGGGGUCUGAGACGGCCGGAGAACCUCCCAGGCAGGGCUCUGUGUUUUGUCUGUUACAACCUCCGUAUGACGCCACGCCACCCGCUGUUCACGUCCCGUCGGCCUCCUGCACAGCCCACACGCUGCGCCCGGAAGGCCCCUGCUGUGGAGAAGCCGGACCCAUCCCCGAGGUCCCCAGCGAGGACACACACUCCACGAGAGCAGCCCCUCCACUCUGCCCAGGAGAGGGGCCGACCCUCCUCGGGAACCGGCCAGCCGCGUGGCUCCCAGCAUCCAUCAGGACAAGCCCACGUGGGGUCCUCCCUGCGUGCUCAGAGGGUCUGUCCAGCCCUGGGAAGCGACCUUGGCCUCAGUUCACAGCCUGGUGCUCAUCUGCUGGCACCGGGCAUCCACCCAUCAGCCCCCGCCCUGUCCCUCCGAAGGACACCCAGCAGGCACCCCCCGGGGAGGCAGGGGCAGAGGUCAGAAGGGGUGUCUGGGACCUGGAUGGCCAGCAGGGACAGGGGCAUUGUCAUCUCAAAGGCCCAACCCCCAGAGGCCACACCAGUCCUCCCAGGGAGUCCUCGAGUCGCCCUGCCCAGAGCCCUGGCACCAGAGACGCCAAGAGCCUGUGGGGUGACUCGGAGCAGCAGGUGUGGCCCCGGGCGGGCGGCACCGCGUCCAGGGCAGCCUCCCUCCGCUGAGUGACACGGGACACCAGUGCCCGGCCGACGCGCCUUUGCAGGAGAAAUGUGCAAACCUCUGUGGAUACCAUUUCAUUUCCAUUCUUGUGUUGUCUCCAAGGCCCUUUUGGAGAUAUACUUGGUGUUGGUUGUGUUUUUUGGUUCCUUUUCAGAGAACUGUAAACCGAGGCUGACGUGCUCCACUGACUGUGCCGAGGGGCGGGGGCAGGAGGACGGCAAGACCUAUUUAUAAUAUUUAGCGAACUCGGUCUCCCUCAGAUCCCCCGCGAGGGAGGCUGCUGGACCCACCCCGCUGUCCCCCAUGAUAGAAGUCUGUAAAUACCUUGGUGACCAAUGCCCACUUCCCCUCCUGGGUCACCUCUGAUGGCUGCUGUCCACUGAGAACGUGGGCAGUGUCCAAAUUCCUGUACUGUAAAGACUAAAAGGCGUUUGCUCUGAGACUGACAAGGCGGAAACUUCCAUGUGUCUCCUGCCAGGCUCUGUCCCCCUACGCCAUCCCGACACGUCCCCGUUCCCCCGAAACCUGGCUCAGUGCAAUACUCCCAUUGCCAUGGGGUCCUUCACCAUGGUACUGUCUCCACAGCCCUCAGUCCCCACCCCAGGAGAGGCGCCUGCCACCUCCUCCUCAUCUCCGGUGGUUCAAUCGCUCCGCCUGUCCCCAACCCAGUCCCAUUUUUAUGGCCAAACUGAUUCUGAAACAAAAUGAAACUGCAAACCUCGUGUGUCUUAACUCCCCCCAGGGAUGCCACUCCAUUCCUCCGCCCCGUGGUCUGGUGCGUGACAAUCCAAAGCGCCGAGACGAGGGUGCUGUGUCCCUCAAACCCAGAGUGGUGGGCGCCUCUGAAACCAUACAGCCACUCCUGGCCCCAAACACUGGUUUGCAUCCCAGGUUCCUCGCCCACCUACCCCCGCCACACCCCGUCUUUUUAGAGAUCUCUCUAAUAAAUCGGGUAAUAAGCA